AUGCGCAACGCGUGCGGGGUCUCUUCCGGAGUCUUUUCCUGGACGGGGUCCCUGCGGUGGGUGUGUUUCGGCCUGGCCUGGGCAGGCGCUUGUGCUGCCAGGGCGCCGGGCCCGGGGAGGCCGGGGUCUCGGGUGGCCGCCGGCCCAGGCGCUGGACGGCAGCAGGAUGGGGAAGGCGAAGGUCCCCGCCUCCAAGCGCGCCCCGAGCAGCCCCGUGGCUAAGCCGGGUCCUGUCAAGACGCUCACUCGGAAGAAAAACAAGAAGAAAAAAAGGUUUUGGAAAAGCAAGGCGCGGGAAGUAAGCAAGAAGCCAGCAAGCGGCCCCGGUGCUGUGGUGCGACCUCCAAAGGCACCAGAAGACUUUUCUCAAAACUGGAAGGCGCUGCAAGAGGUGAGGCUUGAGGGGGCCCGGGCGGAGCGCUGCGCAGCUCAUUCCCGCAGAACGCGACGGAGGGAAAGACUUGGGUAGCCCCAAAAGACCUGUAAAGGCAGAUUUGAAUCGAAAUCUUGUAAACAGCUUUUCACAAGAAAGGUGGCCUGUUGAGGGAGGUCUCGAACUUGUUUGCUUGAAAGAAAUUGAUGAAAGAAUUAUUUCAAGUACAAAAAAGCAAAGAUAAACCCUUGUACCUUUUGCAUAAUGAACUAACUAGAAUGGAUUUUACAAAGAGAAAUUUAGCUUAAAAUCCCGAAACCAGGCCGGGCGCGGGGCCUCACGCCUGUGAUCCCAGCACUUUGGGAGGCCGAGGCGGGCAGAUCCCCUGAGGUCAAGAGUUCAAGACCAGCCCGGCCAACAUGGUGAAACCCCGUGUCUACUAAAAAAGUACAAAAAAUAUUAGCCGGGCGUGAUGGCGCGCGCCGGUAGUCGCAGCUACUCGGGGAGCCUGAGGCAGAAGAAUCGCUUGAACCCGGGAGGCAGAGGCAGUAGUAAGCCGAAAUCGCGCCACUGCACUCCAGCCUGGGCGACAGAGCGAGACUCCAUCUCAAACAACAACAACGAAAGAACACACUGGUCUGUGUAGCAAGACAGGGAGAAAGAAGAUUCCUGUGUAGAAGUGAAAAGCAGAUAGCAGACAUGUGAUGGGGUUCUAGCGACACUUACGGUCUUGAAGUAAAUACUAAUUGAGCUCCUAAAAAUGUGCACUCUGCCAUGUGCUCUAUGCCAUGCGUGUUGCAAUCCCCACAAUAAGACUGUGAGGUGGACACUUCCAUCAUCGCUAUUGUACAGAUGAGGAAAUAGGCUGGAAAAGUUUAAAUAGAUCAUCUAAGAUUGCGGCUGGGAACCAGGUGGCUGACUCUGGAGUCCAUGCUUUUAAGGCUGUGUUGUACCUGCUGUCUCCCUAGUGACCUGCACUUCUGUAGAGGUUGCCUGCUCUCUCCUAGACACUCUUCCACGUGCGUCACUCAUACAUUCUUACCACAUCCCUUGGAGCUCCCUUGGAGCUACCUCCUGUUAGGAUCAUAGCUCACUGCUGCCUGGGCUCCAGUGAUUCUCCUGCCUCAGCCUCCCGAGUAGCCCACACGUGUAAUCCCAGCACUUUGGGAGGCCCAGGCAGGAGGAUCACUUGAGCUCAGGAGUUCAAGUCCAGCCUGGGCAACAUGGUGAGAUUCCAUCUCUAAAUAAAAGUAAAAAGUAGUUUUUUUAAAAAAGAAAUGUGAUCCCCAGUGGUGGAGAUGGGGCCCAUAGGAGGUAUUGGGUCAUGGGGGUAGAUCCCUCAUGAAUGACUUGGUGCCCUCCCCUCAGUAACGAGUAAGUUCUCACUCUGCUGGUUCAUUUGAGAGCUGGUUGUUUAAAAAGAGCCUAGCACCUUUUUUGCUUGCUCUCUCACCACGCAACACACCUGCUCCCCCUUCACCUUACACCAUGAUGGGAAGCUUCCUUCGGCCUCACCAGAAGCAGAUGCUGGCACCAUGCUUCUUGUACAACCUGCAAAACCAUGAGCUACAUAAACGUUUUUUCUUUAUAAAUUACCAAACACAGGUAUUCCUUUAUAGCAGUGCACAAUGAACUAAUACAGAUGGGGUUUCACUUUGUUGCCCAGGCUGGUCUUCAACUCCUGACCUCAAGCAAUCCUCCCACCUCAGCCUCCCCGAGCGCUUCUUGAACCUCCUAAUACUCUGCACAGUAUCUCAGUGCAGACAUUCCUGUCUUAACACACAGGACCAGUCAAAUUCCCGUGGGCAGCCCCAGGGUUCUGUGGGAUUUCUUGAACACCAACUCUUCUUCCUUCUCCCAAGAAAGAAAAGCAAAAUAAGUGAAUGGAAGGGAUGUGUGCUAUAGGGAAACUUUGGAGUGUUUUCUAAUUCAUCCAAGAAAGUCAGCCCUUCAGUUCUUUACCUAUCACAGAACAGGUUCCAAGAUGGACAGGAGGGCGCCAGUACCUCGCACCAAGGCCAGUGGAACAGAGCACAAUAAGAAAGGAACCAAGGAAAGGACAAAUGGUGAUAUUGUUCCAGAACGAGGGGACAUCGAGCAUAAGAAGCGGAAAGCUAAGGAGGCAGCCCCAGCCCCACCCACCGAGGAAGACAUCUGGUUUGACGACGUGGACCCAGCGGAUAUCGAAGCUGCCAUAGGUCCAGAGGCGGCCAAGAUAGCGAGGAAACAGUUGGGUCAGAGCGAGGGCAGCGUCAGCCUCAGCCUCGUGAAAGAGCAGGCCUUCGGCGGCCUGACAAGAGCCUUAGCCUUGGACUGUGAGAUGGUGGGCGUGGGCCCUAAGGGGGAGGAGAGCAUGGCCGCCCGUGUGUCCAUCGUGAACCAGUAUGGGAAGUGCGUUUAUGACAAGUACGUCAAACCAACCGAGCCCGUGACGGACUAUAGGACAGCGGUCAGUGGGAUUCGGCCUGAGAACCUCAAGCAGGGAGAAGAGCUUGAAGUUGUUCAGAAGGAAGUGGCAGAGAUGCUGAAGGGCAGAAUUCUAGUGGGGCACGCUCUGCAUAAUGACCUAAAGGUACUAUUUCUUGAUCAUCCAAAAAAGAAGAUUCGGGACACACAGAAAUAUAAACCUUUCAAGAGUCAAGUAAAGAGUGGAAGGCCGUCUCUGAGACUACUUUCAGAGAAGAUCCUUGGGCUCCAGGUCCAGCAGGCGGAGCACUGUUCAAUUCAGGAUGCCCAGGCAGCAAUGAGGCUGUACGUCAUGGUGAAGAAGGAGUGGGAGAGCAUGGCCCGAGACAGGCGCCCCCUGCUGACUGCUCCAGACCACUGCAGUGACGACGCCUAGCAGUCCUGCCCUGCUGCUGCUGCCGCCCCGCUACAGAGGCAAUGUGACCAGUCACAGGGACAGAUCACAUCUCCCCAGAGUGGCAACUCUGGUGAAACCUUUUCAGAAUCAUGGCAGAGGGGCGUGGCGUGGUGCUACUGAGAAGGUCCUCCUUCCUCUUGACUUUGUGGUCUGAAACCUGGUCUUACUGUCCAUGUGUGUUUGGGCCCGGAUGGUCAGGGUGGGGAGCAGGGACGGCCAUGGGCACGCCUGGCCACGCUUUACCGACUGCUGACCCCCUGGGCCAGGUGAGGUUGGGGCCUGUGGGCCGCCAGUCCAUACGGUGCUGUCACUGCCCAUCUUCGGUGACACCCUGGGGUGAGGUGCUCAGCACCUUCCUCUCGAGGAGCCACAUUUUCCUCCUUUGUGUUAGGGGACAUAACAAGCUCUGCUGGGCUUGAGGGACCCAGACCAGGUGUCUGCAGUCAGCUCCUGAGACACAGCUGGCCGGCACAACAGGUGUUACAUCAGGGGUUUCCUGUGGCCGUUUGAACUUUGAGCAUUUAUCUAAAUUAAAUUGGCCCAGGGUUGGCUGGUGGGUCACCCAGCAGAGGCUUCUCCCCAUAGCACGAGGAUGUGUUGCCUGGGCACGGUGACUGCGGUUAUUCCUGGAGGUCGGCAGACAUGCCAACCUUGGGCUAUUUGAGCUGGAGAAGCUAUGUGAUGCUAGCCGGUGGCUUUCUGGGCUAGGCCCCAGUUUGAGGCUCCCCUGGGAACUAGAGCCAGGAACAGCCAGUGGCACUGACAAGGGGACGGAGUCCAAGGCGUUAUUGGGCCACCUGACAGCUGGACAGAAAAGGGGCAGACACACCGAGGAUGCGAUUUAAAAUAAAUGCAGAUGUUUACUUGGAAUGGA